AGAGACAGGUGGAAUAUGGAGUGUUCAGUGUUGGUAAGUGCUAAGGAGAAAAAAUGAAACAGGAGGUAAGAUGCAGAGGGUGGUGGUGAAGGCAAUGGGAGGUUGCCUUGAAAGCGGAGCUCAGUGUAGUCUCCAUUUGAGUUAAAGACUGGAAAUGAGCAAGGAAACAGUCUAAGGAAAGAAAGACUAAUAGAGCAGCCAGCAGAGAGCUCUCUGCAGAGAGAGAGGGCGGACCUGUGUGGUCAGGGAAUUGCAGGAAGAAGGCCCGUGGGGUUAGAGUGAUGUCAGUGGUGGGAGAGUAGUACAAGAUGGCGUCAGAAAGCUCGUAGGGGUUAGGUAUACAGCCUUGUAGGCCAUUAUGAGGAGUUUGGCUUUUACUCUAGGUGAGACGGGAACCCACUGGAGAGUUUUAAGCAAAGACAUGACAUGGUCUCACUUAGGAUUUAACAAUUCUGGCUCCUUUUCGAGCGUAGACUGGAGGGGGCCAAUUAGGAGGCUGCUGCAAUAAUCUAGGUGAGAGACGACGGCAAGGGUGAGAGAUGAUAGACCAGGGUGGUAGCAGUGGAGUAAUGAAAAGUAUGAUUCCAGAAAUAUCCAAGACAAUUUCCUGGCAGAUUUGAUGUGAGGUGUGAUUAAAGAAGAACCAAGAAUGACUUUAGUGUUGUUGGCCUGAGCAACUGGAAGAACAGAGUUGCCAUUUAUUGAGAUGAGAAGGCUGCCAGAAGAGUAGAGUCAUAACCUAAUGAUCCCAGCAAGAUAAUGUCCUGUCUUCUAAGAUGUGCAUCAAGCCUGGUACAUACUGAAAAUCCUAUAAGUUGUUUUGUUUCAUUAUGGAGAUUGACGGUUUCCAGCAGUUAGACCUAGAGAAGAGUGUACCUUCCAAAAAGACUACUCCUAAAAGGAUUAUCCAUUUUGUUGACGGAGACAUCAUGGAAGAAUAUAGCACAGAGGAGGAGGAGGAAGAGGAAAAGGAGGAGCAGAGCACAAAUUCAACACUUGACCCUUCUAAACUUUCCUGGGGGCCCUACCUACGAUUUUGGGCAGGACGAAUAGCAAGCACCUCAUUUUCUACAUGUGAAUUCCUUGGUGGAAGAUUUGCUGUCUUCUUUGGUCUUACUCAACCCAAAUAUCAGUAUGUGUUAAACGAGUUCUAUAGGAUACAAAACAAGAAAAGUGACAACAAAAGUGAAAGGAGAGGAUCAAAGGCCCAGGCAGCUGAGGUUCCUAAUGAAAAGUGUCACUUGGAGGCUGGGGUCCAAGAGUAUGGAACCAUACAACAGGAUGUGACAGAGGCCAUUCCUCAGUGAAGCACCUCAUCCAGGGAGGGUCUGGUGGCAGAUCCUAGCUCAUGAUGGCAGCAAAGACUGCAGUUUCCCUGGAUCUGUUCCUUGGCCAUUGAUUACCAUGGCAACAACACCAGAGGUAGCACUUCUGAGCCAGAUCUGAUCCUAAUCUCUGUGUGACUUAGUCUCAAGCAUCCAGGAAUUACAAGCAAUAAUGAGAGUAAUUUUGGACACUUUCUCAGAAUAAUUUCUAUAUUCAAGCCACCCCACCUCAACUCCACCCCUGUGAUACAAGUCCCAUGAGUACUGACAUUUGCACAGUAGCAUAAAUGCCUUAAGGAACUUUGGGACUGGGAGUUUUUGGCUGAAAUCCUCUGUCAUGGGACGAGGGUACAGUAAAGAAGCUCUAUUCCUCAGAAGAAAAUUUGGGCACCGCAAAGUCUAAAUAAAUCCCCUUUCAGGAUUUGAUAUAGUGUGUACUUCCAACAACCAUCCUGGCGUAGUUGGGGAUUGUUUUACAAUAAGUAAACAUUGCUAAUAACUGUGUUACAAGAUCAUUAUCAAGAUCUUUAAGAAUUAGGUACAUCCCUCCAAAUUAAAACAAUUGAUAAAUAAUAUAAGCUCUAGAAAAAAAUAUUAAUGGAUUAUUUUCUUAUUUAUUUGUCAAGAAAUUUUCAAAACCUGGAAAGAUCGAACAUGGAAAUCAUUGUUAGAUAACACAGGGUGUGCUGGCCAAAGUAACUGUGAUACAUUAAUAGCAAAAAACAAACCAAAAAAAAAAAAAAUGAAAAACACAGGGCCUGCAGUAGUAAGACAUGAGUUCCAGUUUCACUUCUCCCAUUUACUAGUUGUGUGAUUUGAGAUGUCUAGAUUUCUGAGCUCCAGUCUACUUUGUAAAAUAUGGGUGACUUGACUUUGCUUGUUAUUGUUAUACAGAAUUAUGAGAAAUAAUAAUUUAUUGUUGUUUUAA